CUCGCGCUGAGUUAGCCCCGGGGGCGCCGUCUGCAGGCUCGGAGCCGAGCCGGAGGGGGCGCGGAGGCUGCUCGGAGGGUCCAGACUUCUGCACCGGGAUUCCGCGAGACCCUCGGGCCGUUGCCCCAGGGAGCGUGACCCCGCGGCCUCCUUGUCAGCCCCUGGAGCGCUGUGUCGGGCUGAGAGCCCGGGCGGCCGCCCGUGCGAGCCUGGGAGGUCGAGUGUGCGGCGCGCUGGUUGACUUGUCUGUUUUCUCAUGAAAAAGUCCUUUUGCCAGCUGUGGCGUAAUCCGAGGCCGGGAAGUGCUGAAGCUGCUGAAAGAUGGCAGAAGAAGUGGUGGUAGUAGCCAAAUUUGAUUAUGUGGCCCAACAAGAACAAGAGUUGGACAUCAAGAAGAAUGAGAGAUUAUGGCUUCUGGAUGAUUCUAAGUCCUGGUGGCGAGUUCGAAAUUCCAUGAAUAAAACAGGUUUUGUGCCUUCUAACUAUGUGGAAAGGAAAAACAGUGCUCGGAAAGCAUCUAUUGUGAAAAACCUAAAGGAUACCUUAGGCAUUGGAAAAGUGAAAAGAAAACCUAGUGUGCCAGAUUCUGCAUCUCCUGCUGAUGAUAGUUUUGUUGACCCAGGGGAACGUCUCUAUGACCUCAACAUGCCCGCUUAUGUGAAAUUUAACUACAUGGCUGAGAGAGAGGAUGAAUUAUCAUUGAUAAAGGGGACAAAGGUGAUCGUCAUGGAGAAAUGCAGUGAUGGGUGGUGGCGUGGUAGCUACAAUGGACAAGUUGGAUGGUUCCCUUCAAACUAUGUAACUGAAGAAGGUGACAGUCCUUUGGGUGACCAUGUGGGUUCUCUGUCAGAGAAAUUAGCAGCAGUCGUCAAUAACCUAAAUACUGGGCAAGUGUUGCAUGUGGUACAGGCUCUUUACCCAUUCAGCUCAUCUAAUGAUGAAGAACUUAAUUUCGAGAAAGGAGAUGUAAUGGAUGUUAUUGAAAAACCUGAAAAUGACCCAGAGUGGUGGAAAUGCAGGAAGAUCAAUGGUAUGGUUGGUCUAGUACCAAAAAACUAUGUUACCGUUAUGCAGAAUAAUCCAUUAACUUCAGGUUUGGAACCAUCACCUCCACAGUGUGAUUACAUUAGGCCUUCACUCACUGGAAAGUUUGCUGGCAAUCCUUGGUAUUAUGGCAAAGUCACCAGGCAUCAAGCAGAAAUGGCAUUAAAUGAAAGAGGACAUGAAGGGGAUUUCCUCAUUCGUGAUAGUGAAUCUUCGCCAAAUGAUUUCUCAGUAUCACUAAAAGCACAAGGGAAAAACAAGCAUUUUAAAGUCCAACUAAAAGAGACUGUCUACUGCAUUGGGCAGCGUAAAUUCAGCACCAUGGAAGAACUUGUAGAACAUUACAAAAAGGCACCAAUUUUUACAAGUGAACAAGGAGAAAAAUUAUAUCUUGUCAAGCAUUUAUCAUGAUACUGCUGACCAGAAGUGACUGCUGUGUAGCUGUAAUUUGUCAUGUAAUUGAAGACUGAGAAAAUGUUGGGUCCAGUCGUGCUUGAUUGGAAAUUGUUGUUUCUAAAUCUAUAUGAGAAUUGACAAUAAGUAUUUUUAUUAUAACUCAGCCCAUACAUAUAUACUAUGUAUGCAGUGCAUCUGCAUAGAACAGUUCCUUAUCCUUGGCCUUCUGUUUUAUUGUUUUUUUCUUUGCUGUUUUCCCUUUGCUUCUAAUAUUACAGUUUUGUAUUUUGUAAACAAAAAUCAAAUAAUGCAUAUCAGAAUCUUUAUAUGGAAGAAAUCCUUUAUUGCCUUUCCUUUGUUUCCUUGUAAAGGCACCCUGUUCUGUUAUGGUUUUUCAUUAUAUAAAAUUAUUAUAUCUAUAUAUGACAUAUGCUAAAAUUUCUUGGAGAGUGUUAAUCUUUUCUGUGACUAAAUAGCAAUAAUAAGUGGAAAAUUAGAAAUUAUUUCCAGGUAUUAUAUUUGUCACAGGCCAUUGUAAAUACCAAGUAUAUUGUGUCUGCCAUAAUUUUUAAAAAUACAUUCAUUGUCUUCAGUCAUACAGCAAGACACAUGAGACAUAGAUUAGAAAACAUGUUGUACAAUUUUAAUUUACAACUGUUGGAAAUAAAAAUCACUUAAUUUUUUUCCAGUGCUUCUCCCUCAUCUGGUUAUUCAAGAAAACAAAACAGUCUCUGAGAUAUUUAGCUUUUCAAACUGUAAAUAGAUGCUCUAGUGUUAUUUAUUUUUUUAAUCCCACUUGUAUUAUUUUACCUCUAGAGCAUCUUGUAUUAGGACAUGUUAUAUUUAUGCCAGUGGGAAAUAAGUUAUGGCCAAGUUUUGCAAAAACAGGAAGCAGUGAGAUACUUGUUUUUUUCUCCUCACUAAAUAUCAGUAAUUGUCAGGAAUGGUAUUACCUAUUUUCAUUUCCUCUUUUCAGCUUUAAGUUUUGUUGAUUGGGACACUAAAACUGAUGUAUACCUGAGGAAAAAAUAGAAUGUGCUCAUGGUUAGGGAAAAUUAUAUUAUUUUUAAUUUUUUAAUUUGUUUUUUAACCAAGUAGGAAUUUGGGUGUAUGGAUAAGAGGCCAAUCUGCUUCUGUAGGCUAUAGAAGAAAACCAGUUGUAUUUUAUGGUCAUAAUUUGUCCCCCUAUUAUUCUGGAGAUUUAAAUUUAAGUAAAGUAGCCAUCAGUAUUUUAAUUGAAAAAUACUAAAGCCACAUAACUGAGUAGGAUGUCGUAUGAUACUUUCAACAAAUUCCCUAAUGCUGCCUAAGCAUAUGGAUGUUUUAAUUCUUUGCUGUUAUAAAUAGAUAUCUAAUACGCCAGAAUUACUGAUGGUAAAAUUGAAGUUGUGUAACUUGUGAAUUUUUUUUAUCAAUGUUUUAAAUAUUAUUUAAAUCUUAAAAUCAUUUAAAGACUUAUGUUGCCACUGGGUGGCAGCCAUGGCUUCUCCCACUAAGCAACAGAAGUGACCAAAUAUAAUUAAGACAAAUUUUCAUCUCUAUUACAUCUGCUUUUAAAACAUUUUAGUUCAUAUUCUAUUAUUUUUCUAACUCAGUACUCCUUUGUUGAGGGUAAUUAUUAGUAGUUAAGUUUUUAAUGGAAAUAAAAAUCAUGUAUGCUUAUCUUUGCUGUAAAAUCAAAUGAAUAUAAAUUGAGGAAAACUUUAAAUUGUUGUAGGAUGACUAGUAGUAAACAUCAUCUUAAUUUUUAACAUAUAUUUGAUGAUGCUUUCCUUUUCUCUGUAUGUUUCUGGGUUUUCCCCCAGUCUUCCUUAUGAAAAAAAUGUAUGUUUGUAAAAAGAGAACAAUUAAUGCUUUGCAUCACAGACAUAAACUAUUCAUAGUAAACUGCACUGAGCUGAUAUUAAUAGAGCAGACUUUUGAGAAAGUAGGAGUGUAGUAGCACUGGAAACAGAAUGCAAAUUUCUGUUCCAUAAUUAGGUUUAUUGUAGCUAUAGCGCUCCCAGAUAACCCAUGUGUGCUAGUAAUAUCUAUUGUGUGCUCUUACUAUGGUAUAAAAACCUCGCUGGAAGCUACUUAUUUUGUACUUAAAUAUUUUACCAAUUUUUAAAAAGUCUUAAUCCAAUGCUUAUACCAGUGACUGUUUUUAUAAUACUUGAAGUAACUUUAAGAACUGAAACAACCCUGGAAAACUCUACAUAGCUAGAUAGUAACAAUACUUGUAUAAGAAACCAAGUUUCCUUAUUCCCAGCCUGGUGUCUGUAUCGUGACACACUACUCUGUGUAUGCUUGGUUUUAGACUAGGAGGAGAGUCCUGGGAAGGGCAAUAUUACAGAAGUUUUCUUCCACAUGAGGAGAAUGCUUAGUUUCAAAUUUAAAUACAUGUGUCAGAUGGAACCCUGCCUAACUCACUUCUACAAAUAACUUCCCCAAAAUCUUAGAAGGUUUUUUAGAACAUGAUAUAAGCUUUGUGACAAAAACAAAUGCCAUUGUGUCCCUUAUUUAGUCAUAAAACCUUAGGAUUCAGCUGAAUAUAUAUUCACACAUGUAUAUUACACAUAUAUCACUAUACAGUUAACACAUGCACCUUGCACUAUUAGUGACAAAUAAUACUGCUAAACAAAAUAGGCUUCAUGCAAUCUAUUGCCAUUGCUAGAAGAAUAAAUAGGCCUAGCAGAUGGGCAACUUGGGUUGUUAGAAUAAGGUCAUUCUUGCAGAAUAUGGCACUUAAAUUAUCUCCAGCUGUAAUGUCCUACCAUAUAAUCCAGAGGUUGCAUAGAAGCAGAGUUGUCACAGUCUCUGUAGCACGUUUGUGAGAAUUCUCUAGGCAGGCCCAGCCCUUCUCUAGAAGUUUGAAUUUCACUCCCACCUUGUUGCUGGGGUACCUUCUUCAGGGUACAUCUAAACACAGUGGCCUUAUACAGAAAUGUUGUUCAACCCACACAGUGCUUUAAAAAAUUAAUUGCCAACAUUUAAAAAUCAGGGAGUUUCACAUAAAAUUCAGACUUCUUGUUUCCCUUUAAAAAUGAGAAGCUAAUAACAUGAGUUGAAUUCCCACAAGUCAACAAUGAGCUGGAAUCUAAUAUGGAUGGUCCUCUUAUCUUUACCAGUGCACAUGGUGAAAAAAUUCAAACAGUAUAAUAAAGUCUUCUUUCAAGUCAAAAUAUA